CCUUGGGGAAAUGGACAGAUAUCAUGGCUGCAGUGCUGAUGUCAACUGUGCUGUGUGGCAGGAGUCUGGGAUGAAUCACACUACAAGGACAAACAUUGGUCAGGUUGUAGAAGUUUUAAACUAGUUUUAACUGUGUGUUCGUAUAUAACCUAGUUACGCAUUUAUGGAAAGCAUUCCAUUCUGACCUAACAGAUGCAUUUGUUAUAGAGGCAGCAGAUGAAAUGGCAGGUAAACUAGGAGUCAAGAGACCAUUCCAGGCUUCAGCCUGCUGGUUGUGAAGUGGGCAAAGGAGAAGGACCUGCUUCCUCUGUGAUUCCACAGAAUAUUUUGAGAAUCUUGUAAGAGAGAAGUUCUAAAACUACUUUUUCAGGCUAUUGGACACUAAAUAGAUGAGAGCAGUUAUUUUGCUUGUUCUUUCCCAGAACUUGAACUCUCCCACUGGAUUGUACUCAACUGGGCCUUAGGUAGUUUUCUCAGAAAAAUUCAGUAGCUGAUCCACCUUGAAUUUUAUCAAUUUGUAAUGGCUAACAAACUUGGAUAGCAAGUACUAGAAGAUUUUAUGAUUAUUCAGGGACAUAUUUUCUAGCACUGAAUAUGUGCCAGACAUUGUCCUAGGUGCUAGAGCUAUAGUGAUAAACAAAUCAGAUGAAAGUAGAAAUCCAUGCCCUAAAGAACUUAAUGUUUCAAUUGGGAAGGUCAAGUCAGAUAGGUUAAAAGGCAAACACAGUAGCACUGUAGACAUUACUAUAUAAGCUUUAUGGCAACUAGUGUUUGUGCAGUGCUUUACAGUUAGUAAACAGUGUUCACGUACCUUAUCUCACAGUGGCUUUGUGGGUUUGACAAAGUAGCAAUCCUCAUCUCAUAGGUGAGGAAACUAGGGCUCUUUAAGAUUAGAUAAUCUGUCUAAUAGCAUCCAGCCAGGUGGUCAUCUGACUCUAAAUCCUUUGAAGUCUUACUUAUGCUACAGUGCCUUUCUUUUUCCUACAGAUAUUGUUAGGCAUAAUUCAUCAUCUAGCAAGUCCAGAAUCAUCUUUCCAGAGUUCCAGCUCAUUCAUAAUAACAUGUUUCAGAAAUCAGGGUCCUGUAUUAGUUACGUUUUUCUUAAAUGGAGACGGAAUCAAAUGUGACUGCAUGUAGUUUUUCUGUUCUCAUUUGGCCUAUUUUCCAAGAGUAAGGUUAGUAGAUGGCUAUUUGUAGCAGUAACUGGACAGCAUCUGUCCAGUGGGACAGCUGGAGACUUGUCUUUAGUAUUUGGUAAUGCUGACUUAUGUGCUGCUUAAUCUUUUGAGUCUUGAUGGAUGUAUUAGAUUUCUAUUGUUGUGUAACAAAUUACCACAGAAUCAUCAGUUUAAACAACACACAUGUAUUAUGUGUUUGAAACAUUAUUAUGUAUCUGUGGGUCAGAAGGAUGGGCACAGCUUAACUAGGUCAUCUGCUUAGGUCUCACUAGACUGCAAUUAAAUUGUCAGCUGAUAUGAGUUCUUAUCUGGAGGCUUGACCAUGGAAGAAUCUGCUUAAGCUCACUCAGACUGUUGGCCACAUUGAUUUCCUUGCCAUCGUAGUAGGACUGGGGGCCCCAGAUUCUUGCUGGUUGUUGGCUGGAGGCUGCCCUCAGUGUCUAAAGGCUGUUUGCAGUUCCUUGCUAUGUGGGCUUCCUAGCACGCCUGCCUACUUCAGCAAGCCUUCAAGGAGAGUCUCUCGAGUGAGUCUUCCAGCCAGCAGCAGUGCUAAUGAAAAGCAUAGUCACUGGAGGGACAUCAUACCUCUUUUGCCAUAUUCUGUUGGUUAGAAGCCAGUCACACUCAAGGGGAAGGAUUAUAUAAGGGCAUGAACUUCAGGAGGUGCGGGUCACAGGGCCACUUUUGGAUCUGUUUGCCACAGUAAGAACCUUCAUUGGUCCCACAGAGAUAUACUGAGGACUACUAUAUCCCUGGAACAGAAGCACCAGUGAUACAAAGAUGAGUUGGUCCCAGCCUGUGUUAAGGGGCCUGCCUGCGUCUAGGGAUGAAGACUCUAAGCAGGUCACUACCCUACCGUGGGGAAAGCGCUCUAGCAGAGGUGGAGCUAUAUACCUUUCUGGAAUUGACAUGAUACAUGGCACACCCGUACUAGACAUCAAGCCCUACAUAGCUGAGUAUGACUCACCGCAAAAUGUGAUGGAGCCUUUAGCAGACUUUAAUUUACAGAAUAACCAACAUACACCAAACACUGUGUCCCAGUCUGACAGCAAGACUGACAGCUGUGACCAGCGACAGCUCUCAGGGUGUGAUGAGCCACAACCCCACCAUAGCACUAAGAGGAAACCUAAAUGUCCUGAAGACAGAACUUCAGAAGAAAACUACCUGACACACAGUGACACAGCCAGAAUUCAGCAAGCAUUUCCUAUGCACAGGGAGAUAGCAGUGGAUUUUGGUUUGGAAUCAAGACGUGAUCAGAGUUCCAGCGUGGCAGAAGAACAAAUUGGCCCAUAUUGCCCAGAGAAGAGCUUUUCAGAGAAAGGUACAGACAAGAAGCUAGAAAGAGUGGAAGGAGCAGCAGUCUUGCAAGGAAGCAGGGCAGAGACACAGCCCAUGGCCCCUCACUGCCCUGCUGGAAGGGCUGAUGGAGCUCCCCGCAGCGUGGUUCCUGCCUGGGUGACAGAGGCUCCUGUGGCCACUUUAGAAGUGCGGUUUACUCCUCAUGCCGAGAUGGACCUUGGGCAGCUCAGUUCACAAGAUGUUGGUCAGGCGUCAUUUAAAUAUUUUCAGUCAGCAGAGGAAGCAAAGCGUGCCAUUGAGGCUGUGCUGUCAGCGGAUCCUCGGUCUGUGUACCGCCGGAAGCUUUGCCAGGACCGCCUUUUCUACUUUACUGUAGACAUAGCGCAUGUCACUUGCUGGUUUGGUGAUGGCUUUGCAGAGGUGCUGAGGAUCAAGCCGGCUUCUGAGCCUGUUCAUAUGACUGGCCCUGUGGGGUCCUUGGUGUCUCUAGGGUCUUAAGGAGCCUCCCUCAUGUCUUUAAGGUAGCAUCAUUGAUCUUUGGAUGUGGCUUUUGGAUUUUCUGAACAAGCUAAUGUUGUGUCGAGAAGCAACACUUUGUGAUCUCAUGGCUUUGAUUGAUUUGGGCUGUUCAAAAUGUUUAUUUGAAAAACGUAUACAUUAAUAAACUUAACAAAGAGAUAUAAAAUACAGAGAAAUCACCAAAUGCUUUUUGAUCUGUUGAUAUUAAAGAAUCAAAAGGUGA